AGCCCGACCUCACCAGGAGAACAUGCAGCUCGGCACUGGGCUCCUGCUGGCCGCCGUCCUGAGCCUGCAGCUGGCUGCAGCCGAAGCCAUAUGGUGUCACCAGUGCACGGGCUUCGGAGGGUGCUCCCAUGGAUCCAGAUGCCUGAGGGACUCCACCCACUGUGUCACCACUGCCACCCGGGUCCUCAGCAACACCGAGGAUUUGCCUCUGGUCACCAAGAUGUGCCACAUAGGCUGCCCCGAUAUCCCCAGCCUGGGCCUGGGCCCCUACGUAUCCAUCGCUUGCUGCCAGACCAGCCUCUGCAACCAUGACUGACGGCUGCCCUCCUCCAGGCCCCCGGACGCUCAGCCCCCACAGCCCCCACAGCCUGGCGCCAGGGCUCACAGCUGCCCCUCCCUCGAGACUGGCCAGCCCACCUCUCCCGGCCUCUGCAGCCACCGUCCAGCACCGCUUGUCCUAGGGAAGUCCUGCGUGGAGUCUUGCCUCAAUCUGCUGCCGUCCAAGCCUGGGGCCCAUCGUGCCUGCCGCCCCUUCAGGUCCCGACCUCCCCACAAUAAAAUGUGAUUGGAUCGUGUGGUACAA